GUCAGUGCCCAGCCUGAGGGGAUGGCUUCAAAUGGAGCAUACCCAGUGCUGGGACCCGGCGUGACCGUGAACCCUGGCACCUCCCUGUCUGUGUUCACGGCUCUGCCCUUUGCCACACCCGCUCCCGGCCCAGCACACAGGCCGCCCCUCGUGACUGCAGUGGUUCCUCCAGCCGGCCCUCUGGUGCUCUCUGCCUUCCCCAGCACCCCUCUAGUGGCAGGACAGGAUGGCCGCGGCCCGAGUGGGGCCGGGGCUUCCAACGUCUUUGUCCAGAUGAGGACAGAAGUGGGGCCUGUGAAGCCCCCUCAGGCACAGACCUUGAUCCUAACUCAGGCCCCCCUCGUCUGGCAGGCUCCAGGCACCCUCUGUGGAGGUGUCAUGUGUCCACCUCCCCUACUCCUGGCAGCUGCUCCUGGGGUGCCCGUUACCUCUGCCCAGGUGGUUGGGGGCACCCAGGCCUGUGAGGGAGGCUGGUCCCAUGGCCUUCCUCUUCCACCACCACCACCGGCUGCCCAGGUGGCCCCCAUCGUGUCCCCAGGGAACGCUAGGCCAUGGCCACAAGGGGCUCAUGGAGAGGGCAGCCUGGCUCCCUCCCAGGCCAAGGCCCGGCCGGACGACUCCUGUAAACCCAAGAGUGUCUAUGAGAACUUCCGACUCUGGCAGCACUACAAGCCCCUGGCCCGGAGGCACCUUCCCCAGAGUCCUGACACUGAAGCGCUUUCCUGCUUCCUCAUCCCAGUUCUCCGAUCCCUGGCCCGGCGGAAGCCCACCAUGACGCUGGAGGAGGGACUGUGGCAGGCCAUGCGGGAAUGGCAGCACACGAGCAACUUUGACCGGAUGAUCUUCUACGAGAUGGCGGAAAAGUUCCUGGAAUUUGAGGCUGAGGAGGAGAUGCAGAUUCAGAAAUCGCAGUGGAUGAAGGGGCCCCAGAGCCUGCCUCCUCCAGCCCCGCCGAGGCUUGAACCUCGAGGACCCCCUGCCCCUGAGGUGGUCAAGCAGCCAGUGUACCUUCCCAGCAAGGAUGGCCCCAAGGCCCCGACUGCCUGCCUGCCACCACCCAGGCCCCAGAGGCCAGCGGAGACCAAGGCCCACCUGCCACCACCCAGGCCCCAGAGGCCAGCGGAGACCAACGCCCACCUGCCACCACCCAGGCCCCAGAGGCCAGCGGAGACCAAGGUCCCUGAGGAGAUCCCCCCUGAAGUGGUGCAGGAGUAUGUGGACAUCAUGGAGGAGCUGCUGGGGUCUCACCCUGGGGACACAGGGGAGCCUGAGGGACAACGGGAAAAGGGCAAAGUGGAGCAGCCGCAGGAAGAGGACGGGAUAACCUCAGACCCGGGCCUCCUGAGCUACAUUGACAAGCUGUGUUCCCAGGAAGACUUUGUCACCAAGGUGGAGGCCGUCAUUCACCCCCGAUUCCUGGAAGAAUUGCUUUCCCCAGAUCCACAGAUGGAUUUCUUGGCCCUAAGCCAGGAGCUGGAGCAGGAGGAAGGACUCACCCUUGCCCAGCUAGUGGAGAAGCGCCUCCUGUCCUUGAAGGAGAAAGGGUGCGGGAGGGCAGCCCCUCGACAUGGCACGGCCAGGUUGGACUCAAGUCCUUCUGAGUUUGCAGCUGGCCAAGAAGCAGCGAGAGAGGUCCCUGACCCCCAACAAAGGGUCAGCGUGGAAACCUCCCCACCCCAGACAGCUGCCCAGGACCCUCAGGGACAGGGCAGAGUGCGCACUGGCAUGGCCAGGUCCGAAGACCCUGCUGUGCUUUUGGGAUGUCAGGAUUCCCCCAGGCUGAAGGCUGUCCGGCCAACCUCUCCUCCCCAGGACCACAGACCCACCUGCCCCGGCCUGGGGACCAAGGACGCCUUGGGUCUCCCUGGAGAGUCUCCUGUCAAGGAGUCACAUGGGCUGGCUAAGGGGUCAAGUGAGGAGACGGAACUCCCUGGCAUGGUCUAUGUCGUGGGUUCCCACCACAGGCUGAGGCCCUGGAGGCUGUCCCAGAGCCCUGUCCCUUCCUCGGGCCUUCUCAGCCCAGGAGGGAGAGGACCCCAGGGAGCUCUUCAGUCUCCAUCUGCUCAGAAAAGAGGCCUCAGCCCAUCACCUUCUCCUGCCAGCAAGUCCAAGAAGCGACCUCUCUUUGGAAGCCCAUCCCCUGCUGAAAAGACACCGCACCCAGGGCCUGGGCUCAGGGUCUCUGGGGAGCAAUCCCUGGCUUGGGGGCUGGGUGGCCCCUCACAGUCUCAAAAGAGAAAGGGUGACCCCUUGGCCUCCAGGAGGAAGAAGAAGCGGCAUUGUAGCCAGUAGGGGCCGCCAUGGGGCAGACUCUCUGAUGCCAGUCCCCAAAAGUGGGGCUCUGAAGUCUCGGACCCUCAUGGCACCCGGUGCCCCAAAGCAAAGGCUGCUUCUCCUCCAGUGCUGAUCUUGCUGGGCCUUAGCUUUGGAGGGUAGGGGAAGGAGGGGAGGGAGAAGGUGGCUGAACGGGGAGGGCAGGAAGGGAGGGCCUGGGGGGUGGGAAGCAGUGCCUUGGGGGCCUUGUGUGUAAAUGUGAAUAAAUGUAGUUGUUUUGGAAAA